AGUGGCGGUGACCACCGGCUCGCGGCGCGUGGAGGCUGCUCCCAGCCGCGCGCGAGUCAGACUCGGGUGGGGGUCCCGGCGGCGGUAGCGGCGGCGGCGGUGCGAGCAUGUCGUGGCUCUUCGGCAUUAACAAGGGCCCCAAGGGUGAAGGCGCGGGGCCGCCGCCGCCUUUGCCGCCCGCGCAGCCCGGGGCCGAGGGCGGCGGGGACCGCGGGUUGGGAGACCGGCCGGCGCCCAAGGACAAAUGGAGCAACUUCGACCCCACCGGCCUGGAGCGCGCCGCCAAGGCGGCGCGCGAGCUGGAGCACUCGCCAGAUCAAUGACAACAGCCAUUGGAAGCUUAGGAAAAGCGAAUGUAACGUGAAAAAAUAGAGGACACUUUAGCCAUCGCCUGACUUUCUGUUGAAUUGGGAAAGAGCCUCCUCCCGUCCACGUGGGAUGGCCUUCCUGAUGUGGCUCUCCAAGACCAUCCCUGGGGGGAUAAAACCUCACAAAUGCAUCAGGCCGUGUGCUGGGGAUGGUGCAUCGUCACGCCAGGUUAUGCCAAGGACGCCCUGAAUCUGGCACAGAUGCAGGAGCAGACGCUGCAGUUGGAGCAACAGUCCAAGCUCAAAGAGUAUGAGGCCGCCGUGGAGCAGCUCAAGAGCGAGCAGAUCCGGGCGCAGGCUGAGGAGAGGAGGAAGACCCUGAGCGAGGAGACCCGGCAGCACCAGGCCAGGGCCCAGUAUCAAGACAAGCUGGCCCGGCAGCGCUACGAGGACCAACUGAAGCAGCAGCAACUUCUCAAUGAGGAGAAUUUACGGAAGCAGGAGGAGUCCGUGCAGAAGCAGGAAGCCAUGCGGCGAGCCACCGUGGAGCGGGAGAUGGAGCUGCGGCACAAGAAUGAGAUGCUGCGAGUGGAGGCCGAGGCCCGGGCGCGCGCCAAGGCCGAGCGGGAGAAUGCAGACAUCAUCCGCGAGCAGAUCCGCCUGAAGGCGGCCGAGCACCGUCAGACCGUCUUGGAGUCCAUCAGGACGGCUGGCACCUUGUUUGGGGAAGGAUUCCGUGCCUUUGUGACAGACUGGGACAAAGUGACAGCCACGGUGGCUGGGCUGACGCUGCUGGCUGUUGGGGUCUACUCAGCCAAGAAUGCCACGCUUGUCGCCGGCCGCUUCAUCGAGGCUCGGCUGGGGAAGCCGUCCCUAGUGAGGGAGACGUCCCGCAUCACGGUGCUUGAGGCGCUGCGGCACCCCAUCCAGGUCAGCCGGCGGCUCCUCAGUCGACCCCAGGACGCGCUGGAGGGUGUUGUGCUCAGUCCCAGCCUGGAAGCACGGGUGCGCGACAUCGCCAUAGCAACAAGGAACACCAAGAAGAACCGCAGCCUGUACAGGAACAUCCUGAUGUACGGGCCACCAGGCACCGGGAAGACGCUGUUUGCCAAGAAACUCGCCCUGCACUCAGGCAUGGACUACGCCAUCAUGACAGGCGGGGACGUGGCCCCCAUGGGGCGGGAAGGCGUGACCGCCAUGCACAAGCUCUUUGACUGGGCCAAUACCAGCCGGCGCGGCCUCCUGCUCUUUGUGGAUGAAGCGGACGCCUUCCUUCGGAAGCGAGCCACCGAGAAGAUAAGCGAGGACCUCAGGGCCACACUGAACGCCUUCCUGUACCGCACGGGCCAGCACAGCAACAAGUUCAUGCUGGUCCUGGCCAGCAACCAACCAGAGCAGUUCGACUGGGCCAUCAAUGACCGCAUCAAUGAGAUGGUCCACUUCGACCUGCCAGGGCAGGAGGAACGGGAGCGCCUGGUGAGAAUGUAUUUUGACAAGUAUGUUCUUAAGCCGGCCACAGAAGGAAAGCAGCGCCUGAAGCUGGCCCAGUUUGACUACGGGAGGAAGUGCUCGGAGGUCGCUCGGCUGACGGAGGGCAUGUCGGGCCGGGAGAUCGCUCAGCUGGCCGUGUCCUGGCAGGCCACGGCGUAUGCCUCCGAGGACGGGGUCCUGACCGAGGCCAUGAUGGACACCCGCGUGCAAGAUGCUGUCCAGCAGCACCAGCAGAAGAUGUGCUGGCUGAAGGCGGAAGGGCCUGGGCGUGGGGACGAGCCCUCCCCAUCCUGAGUCCACAGGGAGAUCCACAGCUCACGGAGCCUGGCCGCGGACCCCUCCCACCCCUGCCUUGCCGGCCCCUGCACAUUUAGGAUAUGCUCCUGGGUGGGGACUGGGCUGUGCCCAGGGCCUCUGUCCCCCAGGAUGUCUUGUGGUGCGGGUCGGCCGUUCUGCCCCCCAGGGCACCCCCUGUUGUAGGCACUGGCUAGGGAGGGGCAGGCCUCCUUCCUGCCCCUCGAGACACUCUUGGGAGAUGCAUUUUCCGUCUGGCUCACAGGGGGAGGGUGAGGCUUUGCACCCCAGCCCCUGCCCAGGCCACUGUGAGGGUGGGUGCUGGCUGAGCCCCCGGGGCAGCAGGAGCCAGGCAGGUGAUGUCUUUGUUCUCGGCUCCCACAGCAGAGCCAGGUGAGGGGGCGCCUGCCAGGGCCAGACCCAGGUGGGGCAGCCUGAACCCUGCUUCCCCCUGUGGCCGGCAUGCCCCGAUCUUUCACACACUGGUGACCCUGAGAGAGGAGGGAGGAGGGAACCUGGCGGGGGUGUCUGAGGCCGCACUGUCAGCUGGCCGGUCCAAGCCUGUGGCUGGAGCUGGGGUCUGUUUACCUAAUAAAGUCCCACAGGUGCCUCA